AGUUUCAGACAAGCCUGCUUGCCGGAGCUCAGCAGACACCAGGCCUUCCGGGCAGGCCUGGCCCACCGUGGGCCUCAGAGCUGCUGCUGGGGCAUUCAGAACCGGCUCUCCAUUGGCAUUGGGACCAGAGACCCCGCAAGUGGCCUGUUUGCCUGGACAUCCACCUGUACGUCCCCAGGUUUCGGGAGGCCCAGGGGCGAUGCCAGACCCCGCGGCGCACCUGCCCUUCUUCUACGGCAGCAUCUCGCGUGCCGAGGCCGAGGAGCACCUGAAGCUGGCGGGCAUGGCGGACGGGCUCUUCCUGCUGCGCCAGUGCCUGCGCUCGCUGGGCGGCUAUGUGCUGUCGCUCGUGCACGAUGUGCGCUUCCACCACUUUCCCAUCGAGCGCCAGCUCAACGGCACCUACGCCAUUGCCGGCGGCAAAGCGCACUGUGGACCGGCAGAGCUCUGCGAGUUCUACUCGCGCGACCCCGACGGGCUGCCCUGCAACCUGCGCAAGCCGUGCAACCGGCCGUCGGGCCUCGAGCCGCAGCCGGGGGUCUUCGACUGCCUGCGAGACGCCAUGGUGCGUGACUACGUGCGCCAGACGUGGAAGCUGGAGGGCGAGGCCCUGGAGCAGGCCAUCAUCAGCCAGGCCCCGCAGGUGGAGAAGCUCAUUGCUACGACGGCCCACGAGCGGAUGCCCUGGUACCACAGCAGCCUGACGCGUGAGGAGGCCGAGCGCAAACUUUACUCUGGGGCGCAGACCGACGGCAAGUUCCUGCUGAGGCCGCGGAAGGAGCAGGGCACAUACGCCCUGUCCCUCAUCUAUGGGAAGACGGUGUACCACUACCUCAUCAGCCAAGACAAGGCGGGCAAGUACUGCAUUCCCGAGGGCACCAAGUUUGACACGCUCUGGCAGCUGGUGGAGUAUCUGAAGCUGAAGGCGGACGGGCUCAUCUACUGCCUGAAGGAGGCCUGCCCCAACAGCAGUGCCAGCAACGCCUCAGGGGCUGCUGCUCCCACACUCCCAGCCCACCCAUCCACGUUGACUCAUCCUCAGAGACGAAUCGACACCCUCAACUCAGAUGGAUACACCCCUGAGCCAGCACGCAUAACGUCCCCAGACAAACCGCGGCCGAUGCCCAUGGACACGAGCGUGUAUGAGAGCCCCUACAGCGACCCAGAGGAGCUCAAGGACAAGAAGCUCUUCCUGAAGCGCGAUAACCUCCUCAUAGCUGACAUUGAACUUGGCUGCGGCAACUUUGGCUCAGUGCGCCAGGGCGUGUACCGCAUGCGCAAGAAGCAGAUCGACGUGGCCAUCAAGGUGCUGAAGCAGGGCACGGAGAAGGCAGACACGGAAGAGAUGAUGCGCGAGGCGCAGAUCAUGCACCAGCUGGACAACCCCUACAUCGUGCGGCUCAUUGGCGUCUGCCAGGCCGAGGCCCUCAUGCUGGUCAUGGAGAUGGCUGGGGGCGGGCCGCUGCACAAGUUCCUGGUCGGCAAGAGGGAGGAGAUCCCUGUGAGCAAUGUGGCCGAGCUGCUGCACCAGGUGUCCAUGGGGAUGAAGUACCUGGAGGAGAAGAACUUUGUGCACCGUGACCUGGCGGCCCGCAACGUCCUGCUGGUUAACCGGCACUACGCCAAGAUCAGCGACUUUGGCCUCUCCAAAGCACUGGGUGCCGACGACAGCUACUACACUGCCCGCUCAGCAGGGAAGUGGCCGCUCAAGUGGUACGCACCCGAAUGCAUCAACUUCCGCAAGUUCUCCAGCCGCAGCGAUGUCUGGAGCUAUGGGGUCACCAUGUGGGAGGCCUUGUCCUACGGCCAGAAGCCCUACAAGAAGAUGAAAGGGCCGGAGGUCAUGGCCUUCAUCGAGCAGGGCAAGCGGAUGGAGUGCCCACCAGAGUGUCCACCCGAACUGUACGCACUCAUGAGUGACUGCUGGAUCUACAAGGUUUCCAGCGCCCACGCGGACUCCCCUCUGGGCCUCUGCAUUCACCGCUGCCGCUGCCUGGAAAGCUCUCCCCGUCCCCACCGGUGAUGUCCCCUAGGAAAGCUCCCCGUCCCCCGGGGUGAUGUCCCCUAGGAAAGCUCCCCGUCCCCUCCCGGGUGAUGUCCGCUAGGAAAGCUCCCCGUCCCCCCCAGGUGAUGUCCCCGAGGAAAGCUCCCCGUUCCCUCCCGGGUGAUGUCCGCUAGGAAAGCUCCCCGCCCAGGCUCCCUGGGUAUGGAGGAGAGGGGCUGAGGGACGCAGUUUCUGAUCACUGCUUGCACACCUCCUGUGAUGGGCAGCUCAUCCAUUACCUCUCAACGCAGCCUGGGCUGGUAAGUGAGUUACAAUUCUUAGAAAGGUUUUCCAGCUGCUGACACCAACCUUGACCCCCAUUCCCUUUACCGUUCCAAGACCAUACAGAGCACACCUCUUCUCCAAAUAUCUCACUCCUCCUCUAUUGAUCAUGUGCCUAUUCCAGACGUGUGUCAUGAGGCACACAGGCUCAGGGUGAUAACCACUGGCAUGGUGGCAGCCCACUGGGCCCUGGAGGUCCAGAGAAGCUCCUGAGCCAGCUGAGAGGGGCCAAUCUGGUGGGCUUCCUGUAGGAGGGAACGCCUUAGCUGAGUUCUGAAGGGUGAGUGACAUUUGGUUGGGGACCGUAAAGAAAGUAUCCCAGGGAGCAGGAAUAGUGUGUAGUGGGAGAGAAUGUCCUUCUGGAAACAAAGAGAGGUUUUGGCGGGGCUGGAAGGCUGAGUUUGGAAAUGGGAAGAAAACGCAAGGCCUGGUGCGGUGAUCAAGAUGGGAGGUCAGUAACAUCCUCUUUGUUUCAUAUUUCCUGACUCCUUGGCCAGGAAGCAACUAACAUCUCCAUCUACCAGGUCCACGGCUUCCUAGCAUUGGGUUUUACCAUUUUAAAAACAUUUUUUAAUUUUAGAUGGGAAAAAUAUCUUAUUGUGUAAAUUAAGACAAAUUAGCAUUUCUCUUGUAAGUGGCGAAGUUGAGCAGUGUUUUCAGAUGUGCGCCAGCUUGACAGAUGCCACCUCUUGCUGUGAACGUCUCAUGGCCUCAUGCCCAGCACAGAGCUCGCACCUUCUCAGGCCCCAUCCUCUGCUCUGAGCAAAAGGCCAAGGGCGUAGGCUGCCCUGUGGCCACAUGGGUGAGGAUAUGGUGAAUCAGUUUCCUGUUCUGCUUCCAUUCACCUUUUGUCCCUUCAGGGUUUCAAAUUUCUCUCUUCUCUGUUGGAGGCUGGGGUCCCAUGUGCCUGUAGCUUUGUCCUUGUCUGAGGUAUCUCUGAGCUCAAAUUAGAGGGCUGUGAAGCCCCAGGAAGGUAUUUGUGGGAGGCAAUUCUGAUGUGCUGGGUGCCUCGAACACACAACUUCCUGUUUAAUUCUCAAAACAUCUGCCUGGGGUGGGGACUCUUGAACCCAUUUUACAGUUGAGGAAACCAAGGCUCUGAGGACUUGGUUUACAGACCCAACAUGCCCACUAUCCCAAGGCCAAUAUGUAAGAGGCAACUCUAUUGGCAGCUUUUCUGGGCUUCAUUUAACAAACUCCUCUGUAGACAUUAAGGUUCUGUUUAAUUCAUGUUCUAGAGGACAGAGGUUGUUAGCUCUCCAUCUUGAGGCAAAACUCUUUGUCCCACCCUGCCCAAUCAAGGCAUGGAAGCCCUGUUUCUCAUCUAGGAAGGGGCUGUGGUGUUCAGCUCAGCACCAACCUUAUACUUCAGGGAGAGAAAUGGGAAAGAAAAAAAGGGAGAAGAAAGCACAUACAUUCAUCCUCCUCGGAACCAAACUCCUGAGUUAGGCCUUGGUUCUGGCUCCGUGGCUGCCACUAAAAUCCCAUGUGGCCUUGUUAAAUCCCUCCCACCUCUGGCUCUCCACUUCCGCUUCUGUGGAGUUUUUAUUCUAGCAAUGAAACUUUUCACAUAUGAGCUCCUGGUUCUUUCUUAUAUCUGCCUGCUUUUGUCUCAUAGUCUCCUGUUCUUUCUUUUCUUUGAGAUAAAGUUUUGCUCUUGUUGCCCAGGCUGGAGUGCAAUGGCGCGAUCUUGGCUCACUGCAAUCUCCACGUUCCGGGUUCAAGCGAUUCUCCUGCCUCAGCCUCCUGAGUAGCUGGGACUACAGGCACCCGCCACCAUGCCCAGCUAAUUUUUGUAUUUUUAGUAGAGAUAGGGUUUCACCAUAUUGGUCAGGCUGGUCUUGAACUCCUGAUCUCAGGUGAUCCACCCGCCUCGGCCUCCCAAAGUGUUGAGAUUACAGGCAUGAGCCACUGCACCCGGCCUCCUGUUCUUGUUUAUGGCUGUUAUUCCCUUCUUUAUCUCUUUGAGUUUUUAAUAUAUUUAUUGCAAAAUUCUUUUAAGGUUGCACUAUUAUUCUCUAUUUCCUCAGACGUAAAUUCUUCCAGUUGGGGAGUUUGUGGAAAUUUCAUGAAGUGGUUGUGAAUCCAUUGUCUCUUCAGAAUAUUUCUUGCAUGUGUAUCUUGUAAGGGCUGUAUAUGAGAGCCUGUGCUCUUGGCUUCAUACAUUAGGGGGCCCUGCAUUGGUACUAGCCUCCUAAUGGGUAGGUGGUGGGGGGCUUCAACCCUUGUCUCUGGGCAUCUCUGCAGUGGUCUCUUGUAUACCUGGUAUUUUCCUGUCAUUGCUAAGUGUUUGAAGAAUGGUUUCUAUGUGUACUUGGUCUGCCAUCUUGAAUGAAAGUCCAAUUUCACCAUCUGUAAACAUUUCACAGAUGAGGCACCGGAAGUUCAGGGAGGUGGCCUGACUUGCCCCAGUCCACACAGCUAGGAGGGAGAAUUUGAACCCAGCGAAACCCUAUCCACUCCCCGCUCCUCGGCAGGCCCUGGCCCGGUGCUCCCCUCAGCUCUGACUCAUUGCUAGCUCUGCAUUCCCUGGACACCUUCUUCCUCAGAGAGCUGGGAGAAUGGCCUCUACCCUGUAGACACGCUAAAUAAACUCAAAAUUUUGUUCUGGUGGACGAAGUGAAAAAAACCAAAACUGGCAGAUUAGCUCGGUAUAAUAUGACAAGGCCCUGGACUCUGCAGUCUGGCUGUGAGACCUCAGGGAGGUUACUUAACCUUGGGGAGCUUCAGUCUUCUCAUUUGUCACAUGGUGAUAAUAACUGUGUUUACCUUUCUGAGUAGUGAUGUGAAGUGAAACAAUGCAUUAGUUUAGCACUUAGUAGCUGCUUAUUAAAUAUUACUUCCUUCCAUGGAGGAAAGCAAACUGGGGAUGGGGCCAGGGGAAUGUGAUAGCUGAUCCAUCAAAUUCCUGAAAGGUUUCAUGGGCCAGAGGGAGGAGAGCUUCUCCAUGGUCUGAAAAAGAGAACAGAGAAUAACAGGGAAGGAUCCAGGGAAGGUGACACAGCUGCAAAGUCUGUUCAUUGGGGUAAAGAAUAAUCCCUUCAACAAAUGGUACCAGGACAACUUGAUUUCCACAAACAAAACAAACAAAAAGUCAGACCUCUAUCUCACACAUAUAAAAAAACUAACUAAAAUGGAUCAAUGACCUAAAUAUUAAAUAUAAGAGCCCAAACUGUAAAACUCUUAAGAAAACAAAGAGGUAAAUAUUUUUGGAUUUCGCAGUGGAUUCUCAGGUAUAACACUCCAAGCACAAGCAAUAAAAGAAAAAUAGAUAAACUGAACUUGAUCAAUAUAAAAAUCUUUUACUUUUUGUUUUUAAUUUUUAUUUGUUUUAUUGUUUUUUUGAGACGGAGUCUCGCUCUGUCCCCCAGGCUGGACUGCAGUGGUGCAAUCUCGGCUCACUACAAUCUCUGCCUCCCGGGCUCAAGCAAUCUUCCAGCCUCAGCCUCCUGAGUAGCUGGGAUUGCAGGUGUCCAUCACCAUGACCAGCUAAUUUUUGUCUUCUUAGUAGAGAUGGGGUUUCACCAUGUUGGCCAGGCUGGUCUCGAACUCCUGACCUCAGGUGAUCCACCUGCCUUGGCCUCCCAAAGUGCUGGGAUUACAGGCAUGAGCCACUGUGCCUGGCCAAAAAACCUUUUAAUUUUUAAAUUAAAGGACAUCAUCAAAGGGUAGCCCAGAGAAUGAGAAAAAUGUUAGCAAAUCAUUUAUCUGAUAAGGAUUUAGUGUUUAGAAUGCAUAAAGAAUUCCUACAAUCCAACAACAAAAAAAUAUCCAACUCAAUUAACUGGGCAAAAGACUCGAACAGACAUUUCUCCACAGAUGCUAUACAAAUGGUUAACAAACACAUGAAAUGUGAACUUCAUUAAUCAUAAGAGAAAUGAAAAUAAAAACCACAGUGACAAGCCACACCUCACACCUCCUAGGAUGGCCGUGUGCACACACCGUAACUACGGCUGCUGAGGGUGUGGCGAAAUUGGAACCCUCACACACUGUGGGUGGGGAUGUGAGAUGGUGCAGCCUCUGUGGAAAGCAGUUUGAUGUUUCCCUACAAGGCUAAACAUGGGCUGACCAUCGACCCGGCAGUUCACUUUUAAGUAUACACCCCAGUGAAUUGAAAACAAGGUCUCAGAUAAUAGUAAACCAAUGUUCACUGCAGCAUCAUUCACGAUAGCCAAAAGGUUGAAACAACCCAAAUGUCCAUCAAAUGAUGAAUGGAUAAACAAAAUGAGGUGUAUACAUUCCAUGGAACAUUAUCCAGCUGAUGGAACAUUAUCCAGCUGAAACAAGAGGGAAACUCUCUUGCCUGCUACAGCAUGGAGGAAACUUGAAAAUAUGCUAGUGAAAGAAGCCAGACACAAAAGGACAAACAUCGUAUGGUUCCACUUACAGGAAAUAUCUAGAACAGGCAAAUUCAUAGAGACGGGAAGCAGAUAGAAGUUACCAGGAGCUGGGGGGAGUAGGCAAUGAGGAAUCAUGGAUUCACGUUUACAGAGUUUCUGUUGGGAAUGAUGGAAAAGUUCGGAAAUAGAUAGGGGUGAUGGUUGCACAACACUGUGAAUGUAAUUGACACUGAAUUGUGCACCUAGAAAGUUAAAAUGACAAAUAUUAUUAAAUAUGUUUUACUACAAUUUUAAAAAUAGCUUAAAAAAACCCACCACCGCCACAAAAUAUACAGUUACUCUCUGUAAGUCCAGUGAGGAUUAAAAUACAAUGGAAGGUCUCUUGCUCAAGCACAACCAACGUUGUCUAUGCCACAAUUUAUAGACCUGUGUUUUUAAGUUUUGGCUUCAGCAAGGAGGUGAGCAGAACUUUCAGAGGAGGUUAAGGGCUUGGCAGAUUUUGCUGGUGACACACCCGGACAGGAGUGGCCUUGAUCUUGGUUUUCCCAGCCUCCAGAGCUGGGAGCAAUACAUUUCUGUUGUUGAUGAAUUACCCAGUCUAAGGCAUUUUGUUGACAGCAGCACACACAGACUAAGACACAAGAGCACCAGCAACAAAAGAAAACAAUGGAGAAGGUGGACUUCAUGACAUUGAAACUCUUUGUACAAGAAAAGUGUAUCAAGAAAUUGAAAAGAGAACUCACAGAAUGGGCCUAGUACUUGCAAAUCAUAUAUUGGGGAAGAAUCUAACAUCCAACUUAUAUAAAGACCUUUGUAUAAAUCAACAAUAAAAAGACAGUCUAAGUAAAAAAUGGACAAAGGAUUUGAACAAACAUUUCUUUAAGACAUACCAUUGACUCAUUAAUGAGCACAUGAAAAGAUUCUCAACAUUAUUAAUCAUUAGGGAAAUGCAAAUGAGAUAGCACUUCCAAAAGAAAAAAAAAGGUAAAGGAAAAAUGGGCAAAAACAACUGUGGGAGUGGAUGUGGAGAAGUCAGAUCACUCGUGCAUUGCUGGUGGGGAUGUUACAAAGUGCAGCUGCUUUGUAAAACAGUUUGGCAGUUCUUUAAAAAUUUAAACAUAGAUUAACCAUCUGACCCAGGAAUUCCACUCCUGGGUAAUACUCAAGAGAAUGGAAAACGUAUGUUCACACAAAAACUGGUACAUGAAUGCAUUGUGUAUACAGUGGCAUUAUUCAUAACAGCCAAAAAGUGGAAGUAACUCGAAUGUCCAUCAACAGAUGAGUAGAUAAAUGUGUGGUAUAUACAUACACGGAAGCCUUAUUCAGCCAUAAGAAGGAAUGAAGUACUGAUACAUAUGCCACAGCAGCCACUGACCUCAAAGACUUUACCGAGGUGACAGGAUCCAGACACAAAAAGCCACAUAUUGUGUGAUUCUAUUUAUAUGAAGUGUUAAGCAUGGGCAAAUCCAGAGAGACAGAAGGUAGAUAGUGGUUGCCAGGGGCUAGGGGAAGGACAGUGGGUAGUGACUGCUCAUGGGCAUGGAAGUUGUUUUUGGAGGUGGGGGAGGUGGCAGUGUUGAUGAAAUGUUCUGGAAUGAGAGAGUGGUGAUGGUUGCCCAUCACUGUUAAUACACUAAAAAGCAGUGAGCUUUAUACUCUAAAAUGGUUAAAGUGCAUUUUGUUUGAUGUGAAUUUUAUCUCAGUGUGAAAAAAUCCUGCUGUCAGAAGAGUGUCUAUUGGACCUGGCCUGUACUGGCACGAGGUUUUUUUUUUUUUUUUUUUUUUUUUUUUUUUUUGCUAUUGGUGACUGGCCGAGCCAUCUGUUGUGAAGAUGGCUGCUUUGUAGUGUGGAAGGCUGUGGGCAGGACAUGUCUGCCAACUCUAAUGCAGACACUUCCCAGGAACUAAUGACUAUUAGUCUUUGUAAUGCAUCUUGAAGCCAAGUGUCUAGAUUUUAAAACCCCAGUGUGGGAAACACUGACGGUGAAAUUUCCCAAGUAACGGGUGGCCUGUACCUAAUCCACAAGGAUAGAGUGAUAGGCAUGUGGCUUCUCUGCCUGACUCUCCAUGUCUGUGUGGUGUAAAAUAUCUCACCUGAGGCCAUGUUUCUUACCUGUUGAAAGUUUAUUAGCACAGGGCAAUGGCUACAUUAGGAAUAUUUAUUCACAAUGUUGAUGAUGGGGCUAAACCCAGAAUGGUUGGGGAAAACCAGUUCCUUAUAAUCGAUGUGUUGGUACAGUAUUUAUAAUAAAUGAUUAAAAACUGUUAAUCCACUUGGCAAGUUUAAAGCAGGUUUUCUUUGAUCAAGAAGAAGCUCUAUUUUGUUUUUUUUAAGAAGUCAUGGCUCUUCCUUCUCUCUGUAAUUUCGUAUUGGUCUGAUUUUCAUCAGGCGAGGAGGCAACAGGCUGGUGGCUAUGAAGAGUCCGUUCUGCUUCCCCGCCUGCCAUGGGCUGGGCUAGUGAACUGCAGGGGUGUUCUCCAUGGAGCAGAAGAACCAGGGUCUUUCUCACUUAUGAUGCUGCUAGACUGACCCCUGGUGGCCUCUGUGCUGCGACUGGCUGCGUGAGGCCAGGUGCGGGUUCUGGGCCAUCCCCUCACUCCCUGUUCACUGCCAUAUGCUAGCUGGGCGGGGUUCCCUCCCACUCAGGGUGUUCUCAAUGGGGCACCUACCCAGCAUGCACUCUCCAAGGUUCCCGCCACCUCUAAAAGACACUGGAUUCUAAUUUUAUAAAACGUACAGCACCGUAGCACUGUAAGGCCAAAUUCUAGUUUCCAUAUAUAGCUUCCCAUAACAUUGCUCCUGAAAGCGGAGCCACAGGCUUUCCCUCCCGUGGGAGGCCAUGAGCCCGGGGCUGAUUGCGGAUCUCAUGUGCUCUUCUUAGGUCCGUGACGGUUUAGUCUGGGAGUGCGUUUGUAGAGGGAGUAUUGCUUACAGUGGAUGUGACACUUCCCUUUUUUUUUUUUUUUUUUUUUUUGAGACGGAGUCUCGCUCUGUCGCCCAGGCUGGAGUGCAGUGGCGCAAUCUCGGCUCACUGCAAGCUCCGCCUCCCGGGUUCACGACAUUCUCCUGCCUCAGCCUCCCGAGUAGCUGAGACUACAGGCGCCCGCCACCAAGCCCGGCUAAUUUUUUGUAUUUUUAGUAGAGACGGGGUUUCACCGUGUUAGCCAGGAUGGUCUCGAUCUCCUGACCUCGGGAUCCGCCUGCCUCGGCCUCCCAAAGUGCUAGGAUUGCAGGCAUGAGGCACCGCGCCCGGCUGACACUUCCUAUUUUUACAAAAGGCACAGACUAAUAGCACGCAUAGUGCGCUGUCUGUGUGGGAAAGGAGGGAGAUGGGAGUGCUUUUCCCAAAAGGACGUUUAUAGAGCAGGGACAAGGGAAUGAUGGCAAUAGGUCUUUCUAGGCAGCAGCAAGCCCUGCUGGCUUUGGAGUUCCGGGUGGGCAAUGACUGUCAGGGGUCAGGUCUGUGAGAGUUGCUAGGAGCAUGCAUUCUGCAGAAGCGGGAGGGGACUGACGGCAAAGGAAUUAAGUUACAGAAGGAUCCUGAAUGCAUGAAAAUUUGCAGCCCCACAUUGCCUUAACUGGAAAAGGAGGUGGUGCUUUGUGGGCAUAGGAAUCUGAUGCAGCCUCCUCUCCCUGCUGCAAAAUAUCUGGCUGGGAGGAAUGGUCCAAAUCCAGUCCCUCUAAGAACCUUGUCCCUGGACAUGCUGCCGCAGUUCUGCUGAGAGGCGGGGCUGAGGCAAACGGGAGCCCAGGCUGGCGGUGGACCCAGUGGUGAGGGUGGGAGGGAUGAGGGCGUGGGAGGAGGGGCCCCAGGCAGUGGCAAGGAGCUCAGGAGGCUCCAGAUUGGUGGCCUCAUGCCCCCUGCCAAAUGAGUUCCAUCCCCAUCAGGAAGUUGCCAUUUCUAGGGGUUUAACACUGGGAAAUGUCUUUGGAAUACCACAGUAACAGACAAUAGGAAGUGCUACCACUUAUUUAUUUGGCCUCAUGUUUCACACCAUCCUCCUGAGGAUGUUUGUUUUGCAUAUAGGGAAACUGAGGCUCUGAGAGGGGCAGAGUGUGCCCAAGGGCCAUGAUCAGUAAAUGGCAGAGCCAGGACUGGAACCCAGGCCACACUCAUCCAUGCCACUGCACUCAUGUGUACACCCAAAUGGUCAACGCCCUUCCCCGCAGUGCAGCAGCAACGCACCGCAGUUAAAGCAGCUGGGCUUGUUGCUCCCUGCAGCAAGGGGGACCCAAACAACAGUGAGCUGGGGUGUCUCCUAAGAGGGUGUCAGGAAGUAGCAAUUGUAGGAUGUGGGCCUUGGUUAUUAGCUUAUUUGGGGGGUGGGUCUAUGGAGUCAGGGGUUUGCUCUGGAGUGGAGGCUGGCUCAAGAGUGUCUAAUGAACGCAGUCUAUAGUUACACCAGAGUUAACAGUUUUUUCCUGUCUGUUGUAAAGCGAGUUGUUGAAUCGCAUGAUGAAAGAAAUGGUGUGCAGUACCAUCUAAAACUCUAGACAGGAGAUACUAGCCAACCAUUUACAGGUAAUUACGAGAAACGCAAGGACUGUUAGUCCUCGUAACAGGUCUGCAAGACAAGGGCCUAGAGCGCCUCCAGGUAAUGGGCGCAUGUUCCAGAAGCCAGCUGGGUUGGCUUUAGAGGUCAAGGCUUUUUCUAAUAGUCACAAACUGUCCUGUUCCCCUGUGGUGUUUUUCUAGGUAUAAAAAAGGAGUAUUUGUUAUGGCAUGACCUGUCCCUUUGCUGGCUAAGAGGAAAAUAAAGCUUAUAUGACUGUCCUUGAUAACUCUAAAGAAUGGACUUAGAUUAGUCGGUUGGACUUUCAGAGCAGAGUGGUCUCGUUUAUGGCUUCAGCUAAAAUUACCAACUAGUUUUGAACUCUCUCUCUAGUCGUUUUAUUCCUUUGGUGGGAACUGGAGUUUGCAGAGUAUGCAUGAAGAGCAAAUCAAGGAUCGCUACUGGAAGGUUUUGGAAUCAUCUAUGAUAAUUUUACGCUGGAUUGCUGGGUAUUCUUUCAAAGAAUGGAUUACUGGAGACGUGGGUGUUGUAAAUAUCUGAACAUAUCUAACCACUCUGAAUAUACAUGAGUGUGUGGCAGACCAAUAUAAGCCUGACAUGGGCUAAUAAGAUGUAGUGUCCCACUGAAGCACAGAUCGUAUGGGGAGCAUAUUAUUAUAAUAGCAAUAAAUUUCGUGUCUUUGUGUGCCUUUUGUACAGAAGCUGUAGAUCACGUAGAGGCGGGUGUGUUUUGGAUAUACUGUAUAGUUCAUAUUUAUGUUGAGAUAAAGCUGGAAAUAAAAUGUAAUCAUGUAGAAUCUAAGAUGGGAUGAAGCUUCAAACUGUAUACAGUGGCAUGUUAUGAAUUCAUAAGAAGCAACAUGGGACCUAGAGGUGGUUGAUCGUAUAAUGCUAAUGGUAAUUUCUUAAGAUGUAGAAUUUUGGAGGUUUCUGAGAGGUAUGCUAUUUUUAAAAAAAUUCCAUUAGUUCUGUUUUUCUAGAGGACUGGAGAAAACAAGGACAGUGAAAUCUCUGGAUUAAAGGCACAACUUCAGUGUUUCUUAAUAACAGUAUGUCUUAGUCCCUUUGUGUUGCUGUAAAGGAACACCUGAGGCUGAGUAAUGUGUGAAGAGGUUUAUUUGGCUCAGGGUUCUGCAGGCUGUAGAGGCAGCAGCAUUGGCUUCUGCUGAGGGCCUUGGGCUGGGUGCACUCCUGGUGGAGGUGAAGGAGAGCCCCGUGCAGACCACACGGUGAGAAAGGGAGGAAGAGGGAGGUGGGGGAAGGUGCCAAGCUCUUUUCAACAACUAGUUCUUGUGGGCACUAAGGGUGAGCACUUAGUCCCAUGAGAAUGGCACCAAGCCAUUCACGAGGGCUCCAUCCCCUCCACCAAGCCCCACCUUCCACACUGGGGAUCAUAUUUCAACAAGAGACUCAGCAGGGCCAAACAAACCACAGCAUUGGUCUGGAAAAAGGAGUAUCUCUGUCAUUAGAAGUAAGUGGGGAUUUUCCAGGUUGGAAAACAAAAUCAAGCACUUUUUGUCACUCUGGCAGGGAAAUUUUCAAUCCACAGUGAAUAUAAACAAACAAUAACCAGAAUGUAUUUAUAAUCCACGGCAGAAGGCAUUUGUAUGGAGUCUACUUGGAGGGGUCUGAAGGGCCUUCAAGCUCUCCAGUUCCUGCUCACGUCUACAUUUAAAUGUUUUAUCAGGAUUUCAUUCACAGGGGGAUGUUUUGUAACCAUUAUUGGCAAUACCUCUAAAAUUACCUGGCUUAAUUAAUAUUGUUGCCAAUUUAUUUUUACAGCUAUCUAAUUAUGGGUAACAUCAUGAAGAAUUUUUGUUAGAUUCCACUAUCACCUUUUUUCAUGACAUCAGCUGGCCCUCCUAAGAUGUAAAAGGCAUCAGAACUUUCCCCAUUUUCUUUUUUCAAACCAGGGGCUUGUUCUGACACUAAUAGCAGCCUCUGAAUUUCUCAAGACCGGUGAGAUCACAGGAGUGUUUCUAUAGGCUGAUCUUGUUUCUUUAGCACAGUGGUCAGCCCAAACACUGCCAUUAGGAUCUGAGUCUUUGUAUUUGAAUGACCUUUUACUAUUACUAUAGCUAAGAUAGCAAAGCAUCUAAAAUGUCUUUGUUAUCCAACUUCUACAGGCAUUUGUCAGGGUUAGAAGCCUGUUCCUAAAGCAUUCAAAUUUUGUGGACUAGCCCCAAUCACAUUUAUUUAUACUAUCAAUAUAAACAUUUGUUCUUUUAUUUUUUCCAACCUGCCCAUGUGGGAGCAAAUGUUUUAGUCAUCUGUGAUGACCUAAUUUCUGGGAUUGGUCUAUAUUUUAAGGGUGAAUUUAACUCUGUGGUAGCAUUUUGAAAUAGGAACAAGUAAAAUUAGGACAAGGCUACUCAAAGGCAUCUCUAACAAAAUUACUAAAGCGUAUUUUUUACAUUGAGAGUUAAUAAUUUGGUGACAAAAAGGAAUCUUUCUUCAAAUUUAGCAUAACUAAAUCACUUUACUUGUGUGAAAAUAAUUCAAAAUCAAAGCUGUUGAAAUUUUAUUUAGAGCCUUAAAGGAAUGUGAUGAUGAGGCCUGAGUCAUGCAACAGGCACCUAUAACCUGUUUCUCUGAUCAUAGACUAUCCUUUUUCUUUACCUACACUGUUUUGUAAAAUGUUAUAAAAAACUCAUGGGCAGCAGGGAAGACCCCUUUCCUCCUAACUGUUGAUCGUCAUUAUAAUUUCCCUCUUUCUUCUCUUACACAAGGACCUCACAACUACUAUACUCUCUAAAUCACAAUGUUAAAUAUAGUCUUUUCAAUUGGAAAGAAAAAACAUCAAGCUGUAACUAAUCAAAUUGCUGUAGCUCAUAAGCCAGACUCAUAUGGAAAAUGCCGUGAUUCCACUAAAUGUGUUUUCUGCCUGUAUAAAAGAGACCUUAACCUUUUAGCUCCGGAACACUGACCCCUUUCCUUUGGAGUCUGUGUUUCCCGGAUGGCUAAAACAGUCUUUUAAAUGAGAUUCUGAUCCUUUACAUUAUUUCAGGUUGUCAUGAAAAAUCCAAAUUCUAAUUUCACUCCUUUGAUACACAGUUUAGGUAAAAAAACAUUUAAAAAAGAUUAUACCUUUGUUUAUACGUAUUUAUAUAAACAUAUAAGAUACCUGGGCAUAGCAGCUCAUGUUUGUAAUCCCAGCACUUUGGGAGGCUGACGCAGGAGGAUCGCUUGCGCUCAGGAGUUUGAGACCAGAGGGGGCAACGAAGCAAGACCUCAUCCCUAUAAAAAACAAAAAAUAAAAAAAUAAAAAAAAAUUAGCCAGAUGUGGUGGUCCGUGUCUUUUGUCCCAGCUACCUGGGAGACUGAGGUGGGAGAGCUGCUUGGGCCUGGAAGUUCAGGGCUGCAGUGAGCCUAUGAUUGUGCCACUGCACUUCAGCCUGGGCGACAGAGCAAGACCCAGUCUCAAAAUAAAUAAAGACAUCCACUAUCAUUUCAUGUAAAUAUAAUUAUAUACAACCUGUAAUUUUAAAUUCAACCUUGGCCUAGUACAAAGCGACUAUCAUGCCAACAAGUGUUCACUGUAAACAGACUGAGUUGUGUCAGAUCUUCAGAUUUGGUGGGUAUGUUGCCACUCAAAUACCUACCCUUAGAGUAAUUAUUUGGAAAGCACAAGUAACAGAAGAGACCCUUGUUUGUAUCUUCUCCCAAGUACACAGUGUUUCUCUCAAGCCUGCUGGCGAGGCUCAUGGGGUGAAAUUAGAACUUAAAAAAGGAGUUUGGUCGGGGGGGGUCUCAGGCGAUUGUUCUGAUGAAGCAAGUUUAGAAUCAAUUCCUGAGAUACUCUUUCUGAGGAAAAGUCUGCCAAUACAGUUUUUUUCUUAUCUUUUUUUUUGAGAUGGAGUCUUGCUCUGUCUGUCUCCAGGCUGGAGUGCAGUGGUAUGAUCUUGGCUCACUGCAACCUCCACCUCCCAGGUUCAAGUAAUUCUCCUGCCUCAGCCUCCUGAGUAGCUGGGAUUACAGAUGCACAGCACCACCCCCAGCUAAUUUUUGUAUUUUUAGUAGAGACGGGAUUUCACCAUGUUGGCCAGGGUAGUCUAGAACACCUGACCUCAGUUGAUCCGCCCACCUCGGCCUCCCAAGGUGCUGGGACUACAGGUGUGAGCCCCAGCGCCUGGCCCAGUUUUUCUUUGGUUUAAGUGAGGGUUUAUAUGAAGCUCACCUGUAUGUAGAGCUUUACACGUCAUUAUCUGCUUUGGUGUAGAAAGAGAAUCCCAAGACUUGAAUUUGUCCUGAUCGUGCAAGUGCACGUAGGAAACCCUGCUGCUAACAUUGUACAAGGCCUGAUGUCAGCCUACACACCAUAGCUCUGGUUGCACAGGAAAUCUGGUGUCCCCGAGGGACAAAUCACAAGUUGUCAAAACAAUGAGACUUGUUCUGUGAGCUUUGGUAUAAAGCAGAGAAAAGGUCAGGUUCACAAUCACGCCAAAUAACAUUUUGACUAAAUCACUCCCACCUUCAUGGGGAUAGUUUUGAUUUCAUGAUGUAACUAGCCUCCAACAGAACAUUUAUGUUACCUAGCAAAGCCUGGCUUUAACACAGACUGGAAACAAGACAAUGAGAAAAGCAAGUUGGAACAGGCAAGAUUAAACCAACCGAUGCGUUGUGGCGUACCGAGACUCGCCUCGUGUCUGUGUGAACUCAACAGGGACCAUGGAGGAGCUGAAAGUCUUAAAAUUGGAAAAGGGUCAACACACUUCUAGUUAAAAGAAAAAAAAUAAAAUUUAGAUGUGUAGUCUUUACUACUGCACCUUACAGGCUUGGCUAAGUCAUUUCCAGUCUGCACCAAGGCUCCGUUUCCAGCAGCCCCAGCUGGUAUUUCUACAUGGCACCCUGUGUGACUGCCACCUGUGGCUCCAUUCCUCAGUAGCACACAGGUUGCUUUCCAUCCAGCCUGGCUUUGGGGUAUAGCUGUAUUAGCAGGUAAACUGCUAAAGCAUUUUAAUACCAGUGGGUAAAUAGCUGUUUCUAGUACCCCCAGCCCCUGUGCCAUAGCCCAAGGCAUCCCCCCUUGUCUCCAAGCCAUCAUUUAGAAAUGAAAGGGCCAAAGGGGCACUGCAUGCUGUGUUGCUGCUGGUAAGCUCCCACAGGUGGCCCCCAGAGCCCUCCCCCAGGCUGCCCGAGUCCCUGCUGUCUUCCCUCUGUGCCCCUGCUGUCUUCCCUCUGUGCCCCGCUUCUCUCCUUUUCUGUCUUCCUCUCACCAUACAACUUCCUCAGACUGAAGGCUGGUAAAGGUUGGCCAGUGUUAGAACAUGCAGUGGUGAGUUGGACACAGACUGUUCCUGAGAAUGGUGACUGUGACCAGAAGGAAGGCAGCACAGUGGGUGCCAUGUGAAUCUGCGGUCAGCCUGACCUGGGGCCUCUGAGCCAGCACUGCCCAGCCAGGUUCCUCAAGUAUAAUGGAGUAACCCAACAUAUCCCAAAGUGUUAGCCAGGUACCUGACAGAGUCAGUAUUCAAUAAAUGGUAGCAAUUACUGCUUUUUAUGAGGCCUUUUAGGAUAGUGGCAGAGGGAAAACGCUUACUGGAUGAAUCCAAACAGGCUUUCAAGUUGUUUUCGAUCAAGGACCCUCCAUGAUUGCCAUGGGAACACACAGAACUCCAUUAGACUGCAGGAAGUUCCAGCAAUGAGAAGGCAAACCCCGUCUUAACCUGUCAGCUCCACAGAGUAAGGCAAGGAUAAGGUGGUUUACUUUGGUGUGAGAAAAUCCUAAUAAAUACACCUUGUGUGUAAAAAAAACCACAAAACAAGGCUUUUGAAAAAAGCAUCAUUUAUUUCAAAG